GAGCUCGGCUCUUGAGACAGGAAUCUUGCCCAUUCCCCGAACGAAUAAACCCCUUCCUUAACUCAGCGUCUGAGGAAUUUUGUCUGCGGCUCCUCCUGCUACAUUCUGAGUGGGGAAAGGGACUAAGGUGGUCUGAGGACCCCACAGAGUCAGGAAGAUUGAGAGCCUGAUAAAGGUCCUGCGGGCAGGACAGGACCUCCCAACCAAGCCCUCCAGCAAGGAUUCAGAGUGCCCCUCCGGCCUCGCCAUGAGGCUCUUCCUGUCGCUCCCGGUCCUGGUGGUGGUUCUGUCGAUCGUCUUGGAAGGCCCAGCCCCAGCCCAGGGGACCCCAGACGUCUCCAGUGCCUUGGAUAAGCUGAAGGAGUUUGGAAACACACUGGAGGACAAGGCUCGGGAACUCAUCAGCCGCAUCAAACAGAGUGAACUUUCUGCCAAGAUGCGGGAGUGGUUUUCAGAGACAUUUCAGAAAGUGAAGGAGAAACUCAAGAUUGACUCAUGAGGACCUGAAGGGUGACAUCCCAGGAGGGGCCUCUGAAAUUUCCCACACCCCAGCGCCUGUGCUGAGGACUCCCUCCAUGUGGCCCCAGGUGCCACCAAUAAAAAUCCUACAGAAAA